CAGCAGCUAGUUUAUGGCGUGGGCAGCAAGGAAGAAGUGAGGAAGUAGAGACUGGGAGUGUAGAAUCUUUCCAAAAACUUGAAUGUGGAGGGGUAGAUGGGAUAAUGCCGGGAGAGGAGGCUGGUGAAGGACCUCUUAGUGAAGGGAGAUUUGUUGCUGUUUCUGAGAUGGGAAAGAGAAACAAGUUGCAGUGUAGAUGGGGAGGAUGGAGAGGUUGAAGGUGUAGGAGAGAUGGGUCACCAUCAGAUGGGACGUCUGUGAAGGAGAGACCUCAUCUGGCCCACAGCUUGGAAAGGAGAGACUGACUGUUGAGUUGAUGCAAGCUCAGGUGUUGCCAGGCGGGCGCCAUGAUAGUAGAGAGGUUAGGAUACUGUCAAGGGUGUGUGUGGCCAAAGGAGUGGUUCUGUGAAUGUAUGGGAGAAAGGGAGACCGACCACCAGGAAGCACUGGUGAGGCAGGACCCGGGAGGAUGGGAGGCUGCAGCCCGAAUGGUGCCUGAAAUAGUUUCAGGGGAAAUGCUUGGUUCCCGAAUCGGAUCGCCGUAUUCGCUGGAUCCCCUGAUCCGCUGGUCUCUAGGUCCCGGAUGCUGCAAUUCUUACAACAGGACUUGGCAUAGGGUAAGCGCAAAUGCUGUUAACCACACUAACACACUUUUUUUUUUCUUUUUUUUUUUUGAGACAGAGUCUCACUCUGUCGGCCUGGCUGGAGUGCAGUGGCACGAUCUCGGCUCACUGCAACCUCCGGCUCCCCGGCUCAAGCAAUUCUCCUGCCUCAGCCUCCCGAGUAGCUGGGAUUACAGGCAUGUGCCACCACGCCCGGCUAAUUUUUGUAUUUUUAGUUGAGAUGGGGUUUCACCAUGUUGGCGAGGCUGGUCUUGAACUCCUGACCUCAGGUAAUCCGCCAGCCUCGGCCUCCCAAAGUGCUGGGAUUACAAGCGUGAGCCACCGUGCCCGGCCAACAGUUUUUAAAUCUGUGGAGACUUCAUUUCCCUUGAUGCCUUGCAGCCGCGCCGACUACAACUCCCAUCAUGCCUGGCAGCCGCUGGGGCCGCGAUUCCGCACGUCCCUUACCCGCUUCACUAGUCCCGGCAUUCUUCGCUGUUUUCCUAACUCGCCCGCUUGA